GCAGGUUCUCUUACAUCGACCGCCUAAGAGUCGCGCUGUAAGAAGCAACAACCUCUCCUCUUCGUCUCCGCCAUCAGCUCGGCAGUCGCGAAGCAGCAACCAUGGUGAGAAUCGGCUUCGGCUCUUUGUGGCCGUUGGGUGGAGUCAGCGCCCCCAGGCUCUACUUGGAAAACCUUUAAGCUCUUUUCUUUCGUAAGCUCUCUGGGCGAGGGUGGUGGUAUGUUUUGUGAGGUUUAGCUUAGCCCCAAAUCCUCAAGCCCCGCCGCCGCCGCAGUGCGGGUGCAGGAACCGGGCCAGUACUGCGCCCAGGGCGCAGCAGAGCGCUGGGGAGGAACAAAGGCGGCGCCUAGGCGCCUGUGUUAUCCGAGAGACUUUCGGGGGCCGCGGGCAGCCCGUCUGCCGCGACCGAGGGGUCUGGGGCGUCCCGGCUGGGCCCCGUGUCUGUGCGCACGGUUUCGCUGAUGCUGAGGGGCCACUUUCUGUCUCGCGUUGUUCUCUGGGGACCGGGAGAGGAGGAGGCACCCAAAAAGAGCGGGGGCGUUGGGCGAGCUGGGGGACGUGGGAGGGGGAACGGGAACAAAGCGCAGCCUAGGGUUAGCGUGGGAAGACCCUCCGCGGUCUUUGGCGUUUUGGAAAGAUACCCACACAUUCCCGGGAAAACAUGCGUGAGUGCAUCUCCAUCCACGUUGGCCAGGCUGGUGUCCAGAUUGGCAAUGCCUGCUGGGAGCUCUACUGCCUGGAACACGGCAUCCAGCCCGAUGGCCAGAUGCCAAGUGACAAGACCAUUGGGGGAGGAGAUGAUUCCUUCAACACCUUCUUCAGUGAGACGGGGGCUGGCAAGCAUGUGCCCCGGGCAGUGUUUGUAGACUUGGAACCCACAGUCAUUGAUGAAGUUCGCACUGGCACCUACCGCCAGCUCUUCCACCCUGAGCAACUUAUCACAGGCAAAGAAGAUGCUGCCAAUAACUAUGCCCGAGGGCACUACACCAUUGGCAAGGAGAUCAUUGACCUCGUGUUGGACCGAAUUCGCAAGCUGGCCGACCAGUGCACGGGUCUCCAGGGCUUCUUGGUUUUCCACAGCUUUGGUGGGGGAACUGGUUCUGGGUUCACCUCGCUGCUCAUGGAACGUCUCUCAGUUGAUUAUGGCAAGAAGUCCAAGCUGGAGUUCUCUAUUUACCCGGCGCCCCAGGUUUCCACAGCUGUAGUUGAGCCCUACAACUCCAUCCUCACCACCCACACCACCCUGGAGCACUCUGAUUGUGCCUUCAUGGUAGACAAUGAGGCCAUCUAUGACAUCUGUCGUAGAAACCUCGAUAUUGAGCGUCCAACCUAUACUAACCUGAAUAGGUUAAUAGGUCAAAUUGUGUCCUCCAUCACUGCUUCCCUGAGAUUUGAUGGAGCCCUGAAUGUUGACCUGACAGAAUUCCAGACCAACCUGGUGCCCUAUCCCCGCAUCCACUUCCCUCUGGCCACAUAUGCCCCUGUCAUCUCUGCUGAGAAAGCCUACCAUGAACAGCUUUCUGUAGCAGAGAUCACCAAUGCUUGCUUUGAGCCAGCCAACCAGAUGGUGAAAUGUGACCCUCGCCAUGGUAAAUACAUGGCUUGCUGCCUGUUGUACCGUGGUGACGUGGUUCCCAAAGAUGUCAAUGCUGCCAUUGCCACCAUCAAGACCAAGCGUACCAUCCAGUUUGUGGAUUGGUGCCCCACUGGCUUCAAGGUUGGCAUCAACUACCAGCCUCCCACUGUGGUGCCUGGUGGAGACCUGGCCAAGGUACAGAGAGCUGUGUGCAUGCUGAGCAACACCACAGCCAUUGCUGAGGCCUGGGCUCGCCUGGACCACAAGUUUGACCUGAUGUAUGCCAAACGUGCCUUUGUUCACUGGUACGUUGGGGAGGGGAUGGAGGAAGGUGAGUUUUCAGAGGCCCGUGAGGACAUGGCUGCCCUUGAGAAGGAUUAUGAGGAGGUUGGUGUGGAUUCUGUUGAAGGAGAGGGUGAGGAAGAAGGAGAGGAAUACUAAAGUUAAAACGUCACAAAGGUGCUGCUUUUACAGGGAAGCUUAUUCUGUUUUAAACAUUGAAAAGUUGUGGUCUGAUCAGUUAAUUUGUAUGUAGCAGUGUAUGCUCUCAUAUACAAUUACUGACCUAUGCUCUAAAACAUGAAUGCUUUGUUACAGACCCAAGCUGUCCAUUUCUGUGAUGGGUUUUGAAUAAAGUAUUCCCUGUCUUAAAUGAA